CUCUUUCCGGGACAACAUGGCGCCGUCCACGCCGCUCUUGACAGUCCGAGGAUCAGAAGGACUGUACAUGGUGAAUGGACCACCACAUUUUACAGAAAGCACAGUGUUUCCAAGGGAAUCUGGGAAGAAUUGCAAAGUCUGUAUCUUUAGUAAGGAUGGGACCUUGUUUGCCUGGGGCAAUGGAGAAAAAGUAAAUAUUAUCAGUGUCACUAACAAGGGACUACUGCACUCCUUCGACCUCCUGAAGGCAGUUUGCCUUGAAUUCUCACCCAAAAAUACUGUCCUGGCAACGUGGCAGCCUUACACUACUUCUAAAGAUGGCACAGCUGGGAUACCCAACCUACAACUUUAUGAUGUGAAAACUGGGACAUGUUUGAAAUCUUUCAUCCAGAAAAAAAUGCAAAAUUGGUGUCCAUCCUGGUCAGAAGAUGAAACUCUUUGUGCCCGCAAUGUUAACAAUGAAGUUCACUUCUUUGAAAACAACAAUUUUAACACAAUUGCAAAUAAAUUGCAUUUGCAAAAAAUUAAUGAUUUUGUAUUAUCACCUGGACCCCAACCAUACAAGGUGGCUGUCUAUGUUCCAGGAAGUAAAGGUGCACCUUCAUUUGUUAGAUUAUAUCAGUACCCCAACUUUGCUGGACCUCAUGCAGCUUUAGCUAAUAAAAGUUUCUUUAAGGCAGAUAAAGUUACAAUGCUGUGGAAUAAAAAAGCUACUGCUGUGUUGGUAAUAGCUAGCACAGAUGUUGACAAGACAGGAGCUUCCUACUAUGGAGAACAAACUCUACACUACAUUGCAACAAAUGGAGAAAGUGCUGUAGUGCAAUUACCAAAAAAUGGCCCCAUUUAUGAUGUAGUUUGGAAUUCUAGUUCUACUGAGUUUUGUGCUGUAUAUGGUUUUAUGCCUGCCAAAGCGACAAUUUUCAACUUGAAAUGUGAUCCUGUAUUUGACUUUGGAACUGGUCCUCGUAAUGCAGCCUACUAUAGCCCUCAUGGACAUAUAUUAGUAUUAGCUGGAUUUGGAAAUCUGAGGGGACAAAUGGAAGUGUGGGAUGUGAAAAACUACAAACUUAUUUCUAAACCGGUGGCUUCUGAUUCUACAUAUUUUGCUUGGUGCCCGGAUGGUGAGCAUAUUUUAACAGCUACAUGUGCUCCCAGGUUACGGGUUAAUAAUGGAUACAAAAUUUGGCAUUAUACUGGCUCUAUCUUGCACAAGUAUGAUGUGCCAUCAAAUGCAGAAUUAUGGCAGGUUUCUUGGCAGCCAUUUUUGGAUGGAAUAUUUCCAGCAAAAACAAUAACUUACCAAGCAGUUCCAAGUGAAGUACCCAAUGAGGAACCUAAAGUUGCAACAGCUUAUAGACCCCCAGCUUUAAGAAAUAAACCAAUCACCAAUUCCAAAUUGCAUGAAGAGGAACCACCUCAGAAUAUGAAACCACAAUCAGGAAACGAUAAGCCAUUAUCAAAAACAGCUCUUAAAAAUCAAAGGAAGCAUGAAGCUAAGAAAGCUGCAAAGCAGGAAGCAAGAAGUGACAAGAGUCCAGAUUUGGCACCUACUCCUGCCCCACAGAGCACACCACGAAACACUGUCUCUCAGUCAAUUUCUGGGGACCCUGAGAUAGACAAAAAAAUCAAGAACCUAAAGAAGAAACUGAAAGCAAUCGAACAACUGAAAGAACAAGCAGCAACUGGAAAACAGCUAGAAAAAAAUCAGUUGGAGAAAAUUCAGAAAGAAACAGCCCUUCUCCAGGAGCUGGAAGAUUUGGAAUUGGGUAUUUAAAGAUUCACGGAAAGCAAGUUGAUGACCAGAAAUCAGUGCAAACACAUCUUCUGUUAAACCCAUUGGUAUACACAGAAUAUUCCUGUGCCCACACUUAAUGUCAAUCUAUAAUUUUAACCAUUUAUCCAAGAUUCUACUAAGUGUAAAAUUAUUUAAUAAUGUCUAUUAAAUUGAUAUUUAUAUCUUGCAUCCUAUAUCAUGUCAAUAUGUGAUAUAGAAAAGAGAUACGUGAAUUUUUUAGCUAAGCUUGACAGAUUGAAAGACAAGUGUCAUUUUUUUUUGUAGAGGGUGAUAUAUACCAUGUAAAUGAACAAAGACAUUUUAAAUUUAAUCACUGUUUUUAUUAUAAGUUCCUUAGUUCAGAUAUCCUUUAUUAAUUUAUAAGAUGUGUAAAACUACUUAAUUCUCACAAGACUCUAUGAAGUAAUUCUUUUAAUCUCUAUUUUAUAAAUGAAAAAACUAAGGCCAUAAAUUUAAGAAAUUUGUCAGUGUCUCAAAGCUAGGAAAUGGCCAUCUAAUCCCAGAGCCUAUGCUUUAGGUCACUAUGAUAUAUACUACUCCUGUAUCCUCAAGUAAUGUAUCAUUUAGUAACACUAAGCACCCUGCUUAGUUUUCAUGGAUACUGCCAAAUUGCCCUAUCUCAAGCUUUAUACUUGCACCAUUUAAAGUUUUCCACACUGUUGGCAAUAUCAGAAGUGAUAAGGCUUUGAAAUGUUCGCCACUUUGAUAAAGAGGAAAUGAUUGUUUGUUACUGUUAUAUACAUGUAUUUUUAUCAGAGAUGGGUUAUGUACUUUUCCACGUUUGAUAGUUGGUUGUAUUUCUUUAGUGAAUUGAUUUUUCUUUUCCUUUGCCCAUUUUUCUGUUUGGAUGUUUGACUUUCUUCUUAAUUUGUAAGAGUAUCCUAUGUAGUAACAAAAUCCUUUUUUAAAAAUUUUUAAAGAAAAAGUAUACACACAGGACUUUUUUUUUUCUAAUUCAAAAAAUACAAAGGCAUGCAAUGAAAAUUAAGUCUGUUCCACUACCACAUUUUCCAGUUUUUUGUGUAUCUUUCUAAUGAUAGAUACCAUAUGAGUAUUCAAAUAUACAUACACAUACACUUAAAAAAAAAAGAUGGCAUAUACUAACUGUUCUGUUUGGGGCUUUUUGGUGGUGGUGUUUGUUUGACAGGGUCUCACUCUGCCUCCCAGGUUGGAGUGCACCUUGAACUCCUGGACUCAAGUGAUCCUUCACCUCCUCCUUCCAAGUAUCUGACACUACAGGCUUGCAUCACUAUGCCCAGCUUAUACUCACCAUAGUGGUUCUGUACUCCCUUAAAAUAUUCUGGAGGCCAGGCAUGCUGGCUCACACCUGUAAUCCCAGCACCUUGGGAGGCCAAGGUGGGUGGAUCACCUGAGGUCAGGAGUUCAAGACCAGCCUGAUCAACAUGGUGAAACCCCAUCUCUACUAAAAAUACAAAAGUAUCCAGGCGUGGUAGCACAUACCUGUAAUCCCAGCUACUUGGGAGGCUGAGGUAGGAAAAUUGUUUGAACCCGGCAGACAGAGGUUGCAGUGAGCCGACAUCGUGCCAUUGCACUCCAAGCCUGGGCAACAAGAGUGAAACCGUCUCACACACACACAAAAAAAAAUAUUUUGGAGCUCCUUCUAUAUGAGUCUCUCUCUCUUAUCUCUCUCAGGAUGUGUGUAUGUGUUUGUUUCUCUGGAAAACCCUGACUAAUACAGAUUAGCUAUGUAUUAGGUAAUACAUAAUGCCUAAUACAUAACUAAUAUAUGGACAGGAAGUUAAUAGACUGACUGUGCCACCUUAAAACUCGUAUGUUGAAGCCCUAACCUCCAACGUGGUGGUAUUGGGAGAUGGGCCUUUUGGAAGGUAAGUGUGUUUGAAUGAGGUGAAGAGGUUGGGGACUUCGUGAUGGGAUUAUUGUCCUUACAAGAAAAGACACCAGAGAGCUUGUUCUGUCUCUUUGGGCCAUGUGAAGACAUGGUGAGAAAGCAGCCAGCUGUAAGCCAGAGAGUCCUCACCAGAACCUAACCAUGCUGGUGAUAUCCUCAUCUCAGACUUCUAACCUCCAGAACUGUGAGAAAAUAAACUUCUUUGUUUAAACCA